AGCGGCGGCUGAGGCGACUGAGGCGGCGGGCGGAGCGGCAGGCGGCGGCGGCGCGGCAGCGGAGCGCAGCAUCAUGGCGGACCGAGACAGCGGCAGCGAGCAGGGUGGUGCGGCGCUGGGUUCGGGCGGCUCCCUGGGGCACCCCGGCUCGGGCUCAGGCUCCGGCGGGGGCGGUGGUGGCGGCGGGGGCGGCGGCGGCAGUGGCGGCGGCGGCGGCGGGGCCCCAGGGGGGCUGCAGCACGAGACGCAGGAGCUGGCCUCCAAGCGGGUGGACAUCCAGAACAAGCGCUUCUACCUGGACGUGAAGCAGAACGCCAAGGGCCGCUUCCUGAAGAUCGCCGAGGUGGGCGCGGGCGGCAACAAGAGCCGCCUUACUCUCUCCAUGUCAGUGGCCGUGGAGUUCCGCGACUACCUGGGCGACUUCAUCGAGCACUACGCGCAGCUGGGCCCCAGCCAGCCGCCGGACCUGGCCCAGGCGCAGGACGAGCCGCGCCGGGCGCUCAAAAGCGAGUUCCUGGUGCGCGAGAACCGCAAGUACUACAUGGAUCUCAAGGAGAACCAGCGCGGCCGCUUCCUGCGCAUCCGCCAGACGGUCAACCGGGGGCCUGGCCUGGGCUCCACGCAGGGCCAGACCAUUGCGCUGCCCGCGCAGGGGCUCAUCGAGUUCCGUGACGCUCUGGCCAAGCUCAUCGACGACUACGGAGUGGAGGAGGAGCCGGCCGAGCUGCCCGAGGGCACCUCCUUGACUGUGGACAACAAGCGCUUCUUCUUCGAUGUGGGCUCCAACAAGUACGGCGUGUUUAUGCGAGUGAGCGAGGUGAAGCCCACCUAUCGCAACUCCAUCACCGUGCCCUACAAGGUGUGGGCCAAGUUCGGACACACCUUCUGCAAGUACUCGGAGGAGAUGAAGAAGAUUCAAGAGAAGCAGAGGGAGAAGCGGGCUGCCUGUGAGCAGCUUCACCAGCAGCAACAGCAGCAGCAGGAGGAGACCGCCGCUGCCACCCUGCUACUGCAGGGUGAGGAAGAAGGGGAAGAAGAUUGAUCAAACUGAAUGAAACCCCCACACACACACACAUGCAUACACACACACACACAGCCACACACACAGAAAAUAUACUGUAAAGAAAGAGAGAAAAUAAAAAGUUAAAAAGUUAAAAAAAAAAAAAAACCUGUUAACUCCAAGGGAGCACCACCCACAGAACCUCCACCAACUGACAGUUUCUCUUCUUGACUUGCCACCCAUCGCUGGAUGUUGUCCACUUUAUCCACCAUAUAAAACAGUAAGCAGCUGCUAAAAACAAAAAAAAUACAAAAAGUAAUAACAUUAUAUGAACUGUGUUUCCUACUUGAUUAAAAAAUAUAAAGAACUGAGUGUUUAUUUCCCUAAUUAACCAAGAACUUUUGUACACGUUUAAGCUAUUAUUAUUAAAAAGUGUUUGCAAAAUGGUCAAGAUUAUAAUAUUGCUGAAUUAUAUAAAAGUCCUUUUCAUGUUGAGCUAACAUUUGACUUUAGCACAAAAAAGAGAUAUUUUAGAACACGUAAAAUAAUAUUUUUAGUUUUUCUCAUUUUGUUACCAAAUUUCAAACCUUACAUGGAGGUUAUUAUAGUAUAUUUGACACCCUAUAUACCUGUGAUUAGAGAUGUGUAUAUAUAUGAGGGCUAGGCAUGCUGUGUGUCUGAGCUUUGUCUAAAUGUUAUGCAGAAGUUUGUAGAGUUAAAGGUACGUAGGUUUAAUUCAUGCAAGGUAAACAAUAAGUGCUCUCUUUUAUACAAUAUGCAUUGCAUCUGGACCUUAAACUUAUAAAAAUGGUCAGUGAAACUUCUGUGAACAUGAAGAAAUUAUUAAAAAAGGCAUUUAAAUGAAAUUUGCUAAGUUGUGAUUUUUAUGGUUGGAACCAAAGUUAUUCAAAUAGUAAAAGGAAAAAGAAAGAAAAAGGAGAUCUCCCAUAAUAUUUUUCUGCAUCUGUUUGCUUUGACUGAGUAGGCGUUUUGUCAUUAUUGUGUAUAUGAGAUGUACUUGUAUCGUUCAUAAUAUAUUUUUUUUAUUAUGUGUAGAAAGAUUUUAAAAAACUAACGUGCAGCAAUUUCCAGUGAACCUGUACUUGGACAUCAGGUAGUGAGUCUAUUUGUGGUCACUAGCACUGUCUCCUAAACUUGUAAGAGGUCUGAAGCUAUUCUUUGAUUUUUGCUAGUGCUAUUAACUUAUGUAGACCUGUUAAAAAGCAGAGCAACACAAUUAUAGUUAUCCUACUGAGCCAUGGAUUCUGAGUUUUGUUUUAAAAGUGAAAGCCAAGUUGGUGUAUGUAAAGGAUUUCCAUGUAGCUGUGGUGCUAGUUAUUACUGGCUACAUUAUAUGCUAAGUGUAUUUGUGUUCCCCAAGUGUACAAGCCUUCUAUCAAAAGUAUGUUCUAUAACUCAUAUAUUCAAGGUGUAGGGUAUGAAAAUGCAAAGUUUAGGAGAGCACUUUACCAAGCUGGUGUCCUCCAAACUGAAAUUGUUUGUAACGAUAGUCUUUUACAGGUUUUCCUUUAAAGAUGUUUGUGUGCUUUUAAUUGACAACUAACUUCUUGCUGCUGUAUAGUAAAAUAUUAAUAUAUUUUUAUCAUUAAACUGCUGCAUGACUAUCAUCUUUGAGUGAAGAGAAAAUGUUAUAAAAAAGAUGCCUUAAACAGUACAUUUUGGUUUGGAAUUCUGUAGAAAGUAUUUUGGUAAAAAAAAAAAAAAAAAAAAAGGGUCUUGUCUGACAGAGAGUUCUGGGGAUGGAAUUGUUUCUUGGCAAAUCCAGCCAUAUAGAUCUAACUGCUGUAUGUAUAAGACACCACCUGUAGGAGCGGGAAGGUAUCAGUGCUUCUUAUAUUGUAAAGCAUUGGCCUAGGAAGGCAAACAGUUGUCUUUUUGAAGGAUUUUUUUCUGCUGGUCCUUUGGGUUUUGAUUUGAUAUUUUUAUGCUCCCUGGUUGAGUGUGUUGUCUUCGUUUUUGAGAUCUACUGUAUGUGUUGAAUAACAAGCUAUUUUCAUUGUACUGUGCAUUUUCCCAUUAAAUUGUUUGCUUUUAAUAUUCAAUGUUAAAUAUGAGGUGACCGUACAGUAGUUAGGAGUUUCUUUACUUACAAAAUCACUGGAAAUGAUUAAAUUGCUUUUCCCCCUCCCCAGAGGUGCAUUUUUCUUAUUUCCAUAUAGUAAAGUUGAGCUUUUACAGUGCAUAAUGUGACAUUUGGAAUGCUUAUCAACUGCAUGUAAACAUUAAUAACCUGCACUUUUUUGUCUUAAGGUUUGUUGAGCUGUUUUGUUCACUGUACUUUAACUGUGAUAUGGAAAAGACUGCAUUCUCUGUGCUGUUACUAAUUAGGAAAGAGAAUUGCUUUGAUUUUGUCUCUUGUUUACUAUAGCUUCUUAAAGUUAAGCCUUGUACUACAGGUUGUUGGAGUACUCCUAGAUCACUGUUUCAUAGUAGCCAGCAAUAAGUAGUGCAAGUCAACAAAAACACAGCAAACUUAGGCAAAGUGUCCUUUCUUUGAGAUGCGAGUUCUUUCAUGAGGUUUUCUUUAGGGCCAGAGUUACCUAAAGUGAAGCCUUUCUUAUCUAUAGACUUCAGAUUCUGCUUGGAAUCCCACCGGCUCAAGAAGCACAUGUAUUGUGCAAUUAAUUGUCUUUACACUAAAACAGUUUAAUACAAUCUAACUACGAUUUUGAAACCAGUGUCUGAUUUAUGGUCAGUGGGUUUAAAAAGAAAUCCACAUGCAGAUCUUUUAAGACUUAAAAAGUGAUCAUAGAAAAGACUAAGUGACUGUAAAGAUGCUCUUUUUUUAAGCAUCUCACUUUACCUCCCCAAGCACCCUCCCAAACCUUGUCUUCCCUCUUCUGUUGCAUCCUUUCCCUACCCUUCCCUCCCAGGUGCUCGGUACUUUACCUAGUUUCUAUAUAUCAGUGUUUUAUGUUGGAAUUUUUCCUUGUUUUUAUUUUACUAGUUGGUAAACCCUGUUUAUGCUGAAACAAAUAAGGAAAUGGUAUAUUUGACCAUAUGUGUUAUUCAUAGAAGACAGUAUGAUCAAAUGUGCCAAAAACAAGCAAACAAAACUUAAUUCCUGAGAAGUAUGCCUUAUUUUUAUUGAUCUGCUUUGUCUUACAAUUAAGGUCCAAGAGCUUGGUUAAACUGUAUUAUUUGCCUAAGUAUAAAAGAAAACUUGAACUGCAUUGCAAUAUUGACGUUCUUUAAAAUGAGAGACACUGUCAAGUAAUUUAAUCCAGAGAUCAGCCACCAGAUUUGAAAUGCUUAUGUAUGUGUGUGUGUUUGGAGUUGUUUUUUUCUUUUAAAUCACCAAAUUUUUUUUAAGCUACUUUUUAUUUGUGCCUCCUAUUUAUCAUGCUGAUGUUAGAAGCAGCAGUCAUCCAGCCACAGAGGGAGCUAAAGUUAACUAACCAGAACUGUAGAAAUCAUUAUACAUGCCUUUGACAACAAAGGAAGUUCAUAAGAAAAGCCAUGUCGGCUUUUCCUCUACUAGAUACAGAUUGGAGGUAGAUGAAUAUUUGCCAAAUGGAAAAAAAGACAAUGCUAGUCAGAAAAGACAAACUGUUUUCCAGCUUCUCAAAAAGCCAUGGAGAGUAGAAACCAAAACCAACAGGGAAAUAAAAAACCUUGAAAGUCUCACUUUCUAGUUGUCCCAUGCAGGGGUUGAAAUUUGAUUCCAAGCGGAAAGUAUAUUAUGUUUUUUCAGGCCUUCACAUCUAGAGAGAUGGAUAACUUCCAAUUUGAUUUUUCAGGUAAUAGAGAAAGCUGCUAGUAAUUUUAACCCCUGCCUAAAGAAGACAUAUACUUCAUUUGGGAGCAAAUACUUAUUGCCUUGAAAAGUAGCACUGUAAUAGCCUAUGAUAAUUAGUUGUAGAAUAACCUUUAUCCCUUUCAAACUAUGCAAAUUAUUAAAUAAGUGUAAAUUAGGAUUCAAUUAAAGAUAGUUGAUUAUAUUGCAAUCAGAUGGCAUUCACAAACUUAACUGGAGCAUAUACAAAUAUAUUAGUCUAAGUUUUGUAUGCUAACAGAAAGAUAUAAUUUAGCUACCUAUUCUAAAAAUGGUGAAUAUUAUUAAUAUUGUAUAAUAGGAGUGGGAAGACUGCCUCCUUUUUUGAAGAGAGAGAUUAAGGAUUUUUAUAAUUGUUUUUCAUCAAAUUUUAAUAUUUUUGUCAAAUUUUUAGGUAUUUAAUUUGUAAAACAGUUUGCUUUGUACUGGCAUACAGAAAAUAGGGUAUUGAUUUUAAACUUUUUGAAGCCAAGUGAUCAAGUACAUUUGUAAUAAAAGUCAAUGGAUCUAUAUCAGUUGUACUCACUGUUUUCAUUUCUUAUUAAUAUAGGGAUGCUGUACUUUUUCUUAAGGAAAACUGAAUUAAAUUUGGGUGGAAGGGAGGGGGAAAAGAUAAAUCCGUUGAUAAUGAGAAUCUGGGUGGGUAUCAUGGCCCAAGCACUUUAUAUCAUUUUUUAAGUCAGUUAAGAUUUGAUAUAUUUUAAAAGAUACUAUGUCAACUUUUUUCUUCCUAUUUUCUUAUGUAACUUGACGUUUGGGGGGAUUAUCUCAUUCAUUUUUGUUUGUGUGCUUUUAACAUUUUGUGUUUUGGCCCUGUUCAAACUUUCUAAACACAUUUUUCUUUUAUGACAUUUUGGGUUAUCUGCUAGACCUGGUGACCCCACCAUAUGGGCAUGAUUAUUUUUAUCUUCCACACAUGGUUCACCUUCUUGUCUACAAUAUUCCCACUCAUUUUUUCAGGUUAUAUAUACACACACAUUUCCAGAUAAUUUUAGAAUGGGGCUAUCUGAAAUUGAUGGUCUAGUAGCUUUCAUAGCUCCACAAUUCAUUUUAUUUUACAUGUGAACAUAAUUUUAAGAUUUUCUUCACCAUAAAAAGUGAGAUACCAAGUCUAAUGACUUUUUUCCCUUUUUAAAAUCUUUUGAGUAUCAGAAUGAGACCUUGCUAUCUAUGUAAAAGGAUGCUAAAACAAGGGCAUCUGUAGCAACUUAGGUUUGGAAUAGUUGGUGAUGACUCUGAGUAUAACAUUUAUAGUUUAUUAUCCCUAAAUUUGAAUAUCUUCAUAAUUUGGAGAGAGAUGUAUACACACACAUACACAUAUAUAUGUAUAUAUACAUUGUGUGUGUGUAUAUGUAUAUAGAUACACACAUCUCCUUGAGAGUGGAAUAAGUAGGAGAGAUAAUUUAUUGGAAUUGCUUACAUAGAUAAAUUCACCAAAGUUAUUUGUGUAGAUUUGUUAAAGUGUAUCAAUUUUUAAAUCACAAUAUUUCUGUUUUCUUCAUUGCAUAUUAACCAAAUUUUGGCCAUUCAUAAGUAUGCUAUAAAACUAAAGUGAUCACUGCUAUUCACGAAUUAUUAUAGAAUCUUCUUUGCAGAUUUUGUGAUAUAUUAAGAAAAGCUGAUUUUAAUAUUAAUAUUUAAGAAGUUAUUUGAUCCUGAAAACCUAAAUUUAAGGUAUAGGCCAUUUGACACGUCCUUUUUGAACAGAAAUUUCAUUACAGGCUAAGUGAAAAUAAGCCAGAAUUAGCAUGAGUCAGGUAGAAUUUCAUGAUAAAAGAACAACCAGAUGAAAUAAGAAAUAAUGAUUGGUUUCAAGCCAAUGAAUCUGCUAAGCUAACUACCAAGUUUUGAUGUUGAAUGGUCCAGGCAAUUUAUGUCUUUAGGAAAGCUGAGUGUGGCAAAGGUCACUUGUUAACAUUUUUCUUAACAAGAAUGUCAUAACUACUCAUUCAUUUUUAUUUUGUCCCCACGUUUGGUAUUUGUUUUGUUUUGUGUUUUUCCUUCCUGAUGUCCUUUGCUUUUGUGGAAGAUUGUCCUGUUGAUAGGCAGAAACAUGGUGGUGAUCCUCUAUGUAAAAUAUAGUUGCUUCUUACACAUCAGAAGUAUUUCACUCAUUUUGGAAUCACAGGAUUUUCAUGUUUUCAUAAAUACACACAUUGUUUUGAUAAUUAUUAGCAAUUAGCUUAUUUUGUAGCAUUAGAUGGAAAAAUGUUUAAGCUAAAGAGUUUAAUUUUCUUGAUUUUGGUUCCACUUUAAUAAUUCAAGAGGCCUCCAAGUUCAAGGACCAAGUCCUUCUAUUUUAGAAUUGUGAAAAACAUGGAAAUACUCUUGUUAGUGUGUGUUUUGGUCUAAGGUAGAUUAUUAACACAGAAGGAUCCUAGGAGGAUUUAAGAAAAUAUGUCCUUAUCGUGAAGUGGCAGUUAAAGUUAUGGGACAGGUGAAUUACCUAUUCAUCUUGACUAGCUCAAACAAUGAUAGCCAUCAGCUAAUGACUUAUCAGACACAUGUUGAGUUUGGGUCAAACUCCCAUUCAGCUGGAGUGGAUUGGCAAUUUUAAAUGCAGGUAGUUGGUGGUGGUACUUGACCUACCUCCUUACCAUGUACAUCUGGCAUCUUCUCUCUCCUAUCCUUUUUCUUUGUUUCUCUCUCCACUUUUACUCUUGCUGUAGGCCUACCAGUGGCACUCAAGCUUACUUCUUCAGAGAGAAGUAAAGAAAUUUCUGACUCCUGCCUUAGAACAUAGCUAACUGAUGAUCCAGAACAAUUUCAGUAUUAUGAGGUAACUGGGCAGUUUUUUUCUGAUUGCUAUUUUCCCCAUAGUCUUAAGCUGGCAGUUUGAAGGUAUCUAAAUUAAUGUUAAGAAACUUGUGAACUGAAGAGAGUAAGAAGUAUGUGUAUUUUAGGUAAGUUACUGGGAACUGAGACUUACUGGUUUGGAAAUUGGAGAGUAGGACGAGGAGAGCUGUUUAAUGUGUUUGUGGAUGGGGGUUUGAGAGGUAUAUAGAGAAUGGUUUGGAAAUAAAGUGAGAGGAAUUUUUACUAGAGGUAGGAAAAGGUACUAUGAUGGAGUCCGAAUGAGAGUUAUUUGCUAAGGAAAUGAAGUUGAUCUUCACUAAGGAAGUUUCAAUAAAGCCAGAGAAAAUGGGUCCCUCAUUGAUUAUGAGAAAGCUGUUAGUUACUAUAGCUAGAGUUAUGAUAAUGAUCAUGCAUUAUACAAGUCUGUUUUCAUGUAUAGGAUGUCUGCUUUUCUGGGACAAAUUAGCACAAUUGUGGAAUGACAGCUUUUCUGGUCAAGGCAAGUGGAUGCUGGGGAGUUAUUAUUUUGAGGAAAAGAAAAUUUCAAGCUUUUCACCAUUAUUCUUUUUAAACUAUCAGAAAUAUUUAUCACACAUACUAUCUAUUUUCUUGGGCUCUUGUUACAAUGUAGUUUACCUUUACUUUUCAAAUGGUCCUUAGAUCAAAUUAUUUGAUUUUGUACUCCACAAAGACACAUAUUAUUCCUUGCUUUUAUAGAAUUUUGAGACUUUGGCCCACACAAAUUUCUUAGAAGACAAUAAACCAGGUAAAAACACUAACUUGCAAUUUUAGGUGUCUUUUUUAUUUCUUUUACAUUUGCAUCCGUAGCAACCAUUUAACCUUGUAGACCUUAUGAGGCCCUCAAUAAUACUGUAUUUCUAAAAUUAGACAACAUACCCCCCAAACUCAUGUUUCUGUUUCCCUACUUUCUCUCUUACUUUAAAAUUGUAGUAUUCCCAAGAGUUCAGUGGUGGCAAAUGUUAAUAAAAUAAGUUAGUACAUUUUGGAGGUUCUUAUAUCCUUUGUAGGGUAAGCUGAUAGUGUUUAGAUUUCUGUUCCCAUUAUUCCAGUAGUGUUUUAAAUUAUUUAAGAUAAAUAAUUACUGUAAUGUUUGUUUUUAAGUUACAUAAUUCAAGUAUGUUUGGAUUAACUCUUUGUUGUCAAAUUUAGUAUGGAUUUAUUCCUGGUGAUUUGGACAGAUUACUUUGAAGUUUCAUUUUACUCACAUCUCUAUAUAUUAGUGAUAAAAAUCUCUUUUAAAAAUAGCAAAAAAGUGGUUCUGAUUUUGUACUUUGAAGGUAAUUUUUCUUUUUUACGAAUGUCAGGUUCAUUAACAAUAGCAGGAUUAUUUUUACUAUAGCUUAUUUUGUAGAGUUGGCACUUUAGUAUAAUUUUCACAUUUUAUUGUGUCAGAUUUUAAAUUAUAAUAGUUAUAUACUAUAACUCAUUUAAGUCAAUGCAAAGCCUUCUUAAAUAGCCCCUCCCUUAGAAAUUUGUUUAAAAAGAAGUGAAUUCCCAAACCUGUGUCAAGAACUUGUGAUUUAAAUGACUGUGAGACAAGUCCUUGAAAGGCUUAAGUCUAGUCAGUGGAGAUAAAUGAUAGCCCAUUUCCAUGCUGCAUAUAGUUGUUAGGGUUUAUAAAGUUGUCAAUGUGUAAAAGUGCAAAAGCAGGAAAGACUAAAGUUGCCUGUAAAAUUUCUAGUUUUCAUUAUUUGCACUAUUUAUCUUUGCACUUGAUUUUUUGAAAGUUAAGGCUAGUCACUUUCACUUUUGUUUCUAGUCUUUUCUAAUUUCUUGCAGAAUUGUGUUUUCAAUAUUCCACCCAAAGCAAAAAUUAUAUGCAAUUAAAAAUAUUUUAUAAGGCCAAGAAAAUAUUUCUUAAUGUUAGCUGUAUAAAACAAAAAUUUGUUCUGAUAAAAUUUUUAAUAUGGGCCUUUAUUUGCCAAUAAAAUCCUUUGUAAAUGUGAGCUUUAUUAAACUGUUUAAAUAGACAAAGUUAAAGCUUAGGAUAGGGAAUAUAUAUGUAUGUGUAUAUGAAAUGAUGUCUUCGAGUUUUAACUUCCAGCCUGAGAUGGCCUAGAUUUGGUGUGUUAGUUUGUUUCACUGAAGUCAGUGAGAUAGGAGUCUAGCUGGGUACAUGCUUAAAAAGCUGGAAGUGAAGUGGGUGGCAAGUGGCAGCUCCCUCUUUCAUGUAGUUUUCCAUAAUGUUCAUAUAGUUUCCUUAUGGUCUAAGUGUUACAACUGGUUUUCAAGUUGUUAUAUUGAAUAUUCCUUUUUGGAAUUCAGGGUUGAAUCACUUUGAGGGGGAAGGGAAGCAAGGGCAAGAGACUUUAUUUUAACCAGAUGCGGUCUUAUGACCUCAAAGAUGUGCUCUAGAAAGAAAAUAACAAAAAGUGUACCUGUGAACAUAUUUUUUGUCUUGGUGAUAUUAUGCAACACAGUGUUCAGAAUUGCAAAAAAAUUUAAAAAUUGAUAGUUUUAUCAAUGGAACAGAGAGAUGUGUUUUUGGCUAAAAUUAUUUUUUGUAAGUUAUUUGGUUAUUUCAUUUUAUAUUCCCUUUCCCAUAGCUUUGUACACACCUCAUACUUAAAACCAAGUGAGAGGCCUCUUUUCAGAUCUGGUUUAUUUUUGGAAUGCCUGAGUGUGUUUCCAGAUUGGGGGGGGAGAGGUGGUGUUUUACUUUUUGACAUGCUCUUAGCAUGUUUUGCUAGUCAUUCUGGAUCUUAUGUUUGCAAAUUCUGUUGAACAUUCAGUGAUGUAUUUGAAAUGAGAAAGUCCUUUAUAACAUAGUGUGAAUGUUUGUGGCCAAUUCAAUUGUGGAAUCUUAUGGCUUUGUUUUUACUUUGGGUAGAAGUUUAACUUCCAUUGUUCAGAUUUUAGGUUUAUCUAGUGAAAUUGUGCCAGGUAGUUGUCUAAAUAUGGACCAAUUUUGGGAAAUGAAGAUUAAUAAGUGUAUAUUUGAUUCUAGAUAAUCCUUUACUCAAAAUCAUAAGUUAAAGAUUCACAUCAUUAAGAGUUAUCUAACUUUUAUGUUGUCAAAUCUUUAAAUGUGGAUGAUAUUCAGCAUUCUAUCUAUGAAUUUCCUUUAGGAAAAGAGAAAAAUUCAGUCUCCAAACCUUUUCUUGGAGACAAAAUUUACCACAUAUCGAAAAUGAAAAAAAUUUAGAAAGCGAUUUGAUUAUUUUUUAAUGGAGUUUAACCAGCUUAAUUAAUGAUUUUUCCAGUUUGAAGCACUUAUUUUCCCAAUGUGAAUAAAGGGAAAAGAUCAGCAAUUUGUCCCUGGCCUUUUUCGAGGCCAUUUUUAGUUUUCUGCCCCCAUUUCCCAGUCCUGGUAUAAAAUGAAUUACGGGUAUCCCUCUAAGUCCCUAUAACCCUUUUUGGGGGUCACAGAUAUCUUUGAUAAUCUGAUGACAGUGUGAUGGAUCCUCUACCCAAGAAAAAAAAAAUGCCCAUCCCUGGAUAAUUUUGCAUACAACUUCAGGGGCAUCACACAUCUUCUGAAACCCAAGUUAAAGAUCUCUGCUCUAAGUAAAUUGUAGAGAAUUUUAGUGCAAAUCGUUGAUAAAAUUAGGAACCAACUAUUGGCUUAAAACCUUUCAUAUUGGAAUUAUUGUUAGAUGGUGGCCCCUACUAGCAAAAUGUGACAUUGCAACCAGCUUCGUUAGACAUUAUAACAACCAGAGAGAAGGGAAAAAAGCAAAGUUCUGAAAGCUAUUUAUAAGGAGUCAGGGCAUCUCUAGACAUGGGAGCCUUCCUGGUUCAAGGCAGGGGUCAGGGUGCCUGACAAUUUCUAGCAGGGUAGAGUUUGAUAAACCACAAUGCUCAGGAUGCCAAGGGGUUAGCCAUUAUCUUAACCCCUUCCUCACCAAAAGAUUUUAGUUUUGUCUGUUGGGAAACAAGAUGUCACUAGGGAAAAAAA